ACCGCCCCCUCCCCAGAUGGGGAGUGGGGAGGAAGACUGAAGCCAGGCUCCCGGGGCUGCACGCCCGGCCCCUCCCCCUCUCAGGAGUGGGACCCCCCUGCACAUUCUUUUCUGGAAACAGAAACAGCUGUGGGAGGCCCCACCCCCUCCCAAAGUUAGAGACGGAUUGUGGGGGCCUUCGCUAGCUCCCCCCACCCCAAGCUGGCUCGGCUUGGAAGGCGCCUUCCAUCCUGACAAGGAGAAUGCGAGGCAUGAGGUUGGGGUAGCUGUGGGUAGCUGUGUCCUCUCCCCCUCUGCCCUCGGUCUCUCCCCUUUUCACCCUUCACCUUCCCCAUCUCUGCCCUUCAGUCUCCCUCUCCUCGGUCCCUCUGUCCCCUCCUCCCCCUCAGCCCUCUGUCCUCCCGGCACGAGCUGAUAGUGGAGAGGCCUGUCCCCCCACCCCCCAGUCUCUAGGCAAAGCUUGUCCCAGCAUCAGGGAGGAGGCGGUGGCAGGCGGGGGGAGGAGGAGGAGCAGAGAAGCGCUAAAUAUAAACUUCUCUAGUGCUGGGGGUUCCUGGGUCCCUCUGAAGAGUGGAUUAGGGCUUCUUCUGAUCCCCCAACCCUUGUCUUAUGACUUAUCCCCCCACCCCCAGCCCCUGCCAGGAAUACACUUCCUUCAAGGCAAGAAAGACUGAAGCCAGACUUGAUUACUUUCUAAUAGGAAUGAUGGGGAUACCAGGAGGCCCUGCCUGGUCUCGUCUGGGACCUGGGACAGCAGCUGGGAGACCUGAGCCUGGAGUCUGGGGGCCUGGAACAGGAGAGCGGGCGUAGCUCGGGCUUCUAUGAAGAUCCCAGCUCUACAGGAGGUCCAGAUUCACCACCCUCAACCUUCUGUGGGGACAGUGGCUUCUCUGGAUCCAGCUCCUAUGGUCGCCUGGGUCCCUCUGAGCCCCGGGGCAUCUAUGCCAGUGAGAGGCCCAAGUCCCUAGGAGACGCCAGUCCCAGCGCUCCGGAGGUGGUGGGCGCGCGGGCAGCGGUGCCGCGGUCCUUCUCAGCGCCCUACCCGACGGCAGGGGGGUCCGCCGGCCCGGAGGCCUGCUCCUCGGCGGAGCGGCGGGCCCGCGCCGGGCCCUUUCUGACGCCCAGCCCCCUGCACGCCGUGGCGAUGCGCAGCCCGCGGCCCUGCGGCCGCCCUCCCACCGACUCGCCCGACGCGGGGGGCGCAGGGCGGCCCCUGGACGGCUACAUCUCGGCGCUCCUGCGCAGGCGCCGCCGCCGGGGGGCGGGCCAGCCCCGGACCAGUCCCGGGGGCGCGGACGGCGGCCCGCGGCGCCAGAACAGCGUGCGCCAGCGGCCGCCCGACGCGUCUCCGUCCCCCGGCAGCGCGCGACCCGCGCGGGAGCCCUCGUUGGAGCGCGUCGGGGGCCACCCCACCAGCCCUGCCGCCUUGAGCCGCGCCUGGGCGUCGUCGUGGGAGUCGGAGGCGGCACCCGAGCCCGCUGCGCCGCCCGCCGCCCCCUCACCCCCCGACAGCCCGGCUGAGGGCCGCUUGGUGAAGGCGCAGUACAUCCCGGGCGCGCAGGCGGCCACCCGAGGCCUCCCUGGCCGCGCCGCCCGCCGCAAACCGCCGCCACUGACCCGCGGCCGCAGCGUGGAGCAGUCACCACCCCGGGAGCGUCCCCGGGCCGCCGGCCGCCGUGGACGCAUGGCCGAGGCUUCGGGCCGCCGCGGCUCGCCCAGGGCCCGCAAGGCCUCGCGCUCCCAGUCUGAGACCAGCCUGCUGGGCCGCGCCUCCGCGGUCCCUUCGGGGCCCCCUAAGUACCCCACGGCGGAGCGGGAAGAGCCUCGGCCUCCACGGCCACGCCGCGGCCCAGCGCCCACGCUGGCGGCCCAGGCCGCAGGGUCCUGCCGUCGCUGGCGCUCCACUGCGGAGAUCGACGCUGCCGAUGGGCGCCGCGUGCGGCCCCGAGCCCCUGCGGCGCGUGUUCCCGGCCCCGGCCCGUCCCCGUCAGCUCCCCAGCGUCGUCUGCUUUACGGCUGCGCGGGCAGCGACUCCGAGUGCUCGGCUGGGCGCCUGGGGCCCCUGGGACGCCGGGGGCCUGCGGGAGGCGUCGGCGGGGGUUACGGGGAGAGCGAAUCGAGCGCCAGCGAGGGAGAAUCGCCUGCCUUCAGCUCUGCCUCCAGCGACUCAGACGGCAGCGGUGGCCUCGUGUGGCCGCAGCAGCUGGUGGCGGCCACCGCGGCCUCUGGGGGUGGAGCAGGUGCAGGGGCGCCCGCAGGCCCCGCCAAAGUCUUCGUGAAAAUCAAAGCUUCCCACGCGCUCAAGAAAAAGAUACUGCGUUUCCGUUCGGGUUCUCUCAAGGUCAUGACUACAGUGUGAGUUUGGGGAUUUGCUUGGGCUCCCCCUUCAUGGCCUCUGCACCUCCACACUCCCAACCACUGACCCUUCCACAUCUACCUUCCAAAGACCAUCGUUUUCUCUGCUUCCAAAGACCCCCCUCACUCUCCCCACUCCUAACAGUCUUGGUUGAAAAGGCUCCCCCACCACCACCGAGAGGAAUGGGGAGGAGCCCUGUUUGACCCAGUUCAGCUUCUAGCUUGGAAGCCCUUGGGCAAGACAGUUCCCCUUCUCUGGGCGUCACUUUCCUCAUCUGUACAGUAAGUGUCCAUGUAUGCAAAAGGGGUAAUUCGGUUUGAAUUUCCCCGUUUUAGUUUAGAAGCCUAGUCUGUUUGUUCCCCUCCACCGCUCUCCCUCUCAUUCCUGAUGAGCCCUCUCAUUCCUCCUUUCCUUGCCCAGCUAUGGCCCCCUCUCAUUCACAAAGUGCCCCCUCCAUGUCCCUGGACCCUUAAGAUAUCCCCUUGGCACCCUGGUCAGAGACUCUGUGUCUGACUCAGGUGGUCCCUGCAGAGUGCCCUGGGAAGGGAAGGAGCACUGAUUUGGGGGUUUUGAGGGUCAAGUAGGGGUUGGUAACACCUGGAAAGAAGGACUCUUUCACUUCGAUCCCUGGACAAUUAUGGAGGAUUCGGAGGUAGAAGAGGGGAAGGAAGAUGGUUUCUAUCUCAUGACCCCCACUCCCUGUGAGAGGGAAUGGGGGAAGCCUGAUGACCCUCAGCUGUUCCAAUCUAGUAUUUUUUUUCUUUUUUAAAAUUACUGUAUUUAUUAUGACGAUGGUGACUCCCCAGUGCAAAGGGGGGCCAGAUUCUGUGUGUUUCUCUAACCUCUUUGUAAAUAAAUGCACAGUGUAACAUAUGUGGUGGACUCUCACUGAAUGAUUAAAUGGGAGAAAUGCUCUUUUUCCUUUGGACUAACA